UCACUGUGUUGUCUAGGCUGGUCUCAAACUCUUGGCCUCAAGUGAUCCUCCCACCUUGGCCUCCCAGAGUGCUGGAUUAUAGUCAUGAACCACCAUGGCCGGCCCUGAAAACUACUUUUCUACUUCCCUUAUGGUGGCCACCCUUCUCAUCUUCAUGAUUUGAAUAUUAACAUAAAGAUAAAUUUAGCAACAUGUAGGGGCUACACGUAGGCUCAGGUCCUUAGGCCUGGCAUGUUGGAGCAGAAAGAAACACCUAAUUGCAUCAAAACCACUCUAAGUUCAUGUAUGUGGAGCCCAUCAAGCUGAAAGCAUCCAGACAGCAUCUGCUGUUAUCAAAUCACUCGUGAAUCCAGCUAAUUAAAAUAGAGCUUCAUUUUUCUGAACCAUUGUUUGGCAGGAAUUCGAAACGGGUCUAACCCAAUUUCUGCAUGUUUAUGAGCCUUUAUUAUAUCAGAGGUACUUUUCUGUAAAUGUACAGGGCAGCGUUAAAUGAAUUGAUCCACACAGUAUCACUGUAGACGCACUAUGGACUUGCUAAUGAUUUCUCUUCCAGCUUUCUGGUUUCCAGACAUACUCUUGAAAGCUUUAUCUUCUCUUUUUCUAUCCUCUGCUCUUUGCCGUUGUCUUUUUUUUUUUUUUUAAACAUUUUGAACUUUCCUUUUACUUUUUAAUCUUCUUUUUUCUUUGGAAACAGGAAAACUAUCCCCUUAAAGAAGUUUUCUUUUCCAUUUCUCUUUUUCUUCCUCUCUUCCUGUUUUUGUUUUUCUUCUAGUGGAUAAGAUUUGUCUUUUCUUCCUUUAUUUCUUGCUGUUUUCUAUUCUCUCCUUUUCUUUUCUUUUUCUCUCUUAUCUUUUCUCCCUUUUAUACUUUCUCCCAUUCCUUUUCUCUAACCUUCUCUUUCUCCUUUUUCUCUUCUUUCUAUCUCCUCCCAUUUUCCCUAAUAAAAUAUCCUUAUACCUUUGUCUCCACAUGCAAAUACUGACUAGGGAAGAUGGGGGUGCCCGUGGAGGCAGAGCUAUCUGGCUGCUCUAAGAUGAUGUCAGCUGAGUUUACUUCUCUGAAUUUGCUUUCAUGCUUUAUUUUAGGUUUUAAAAAGAUUUUUCAAGCCACAUCUACUCUACUUUAUAGUCUGUAAUCCUACUUUGAAGAUGAAAAGUGUUACAUAAAUGCUAACUAAUUAUUCCUUAUACCACUUUGUGAGUCUCUAAGCAGUAUUAGUUCCAGUUUACAGAUGAGGAAGCAGGAACGGGAAAGGUAAGUAGCUCUGAAAGUUACUGAAGAAGUUGGUGACUGAGUUAGAAUUAAACCUGGCUCAUCUUUGGCUUUGCUUUUUGAUUACCACCUUAUGGGUGUUGACUUUUUUCCCCCCUAAGAAUCAUACAUAUUUAAGGUGAGGUUGAGUGAAUACCAUCCCCUUGGCCCCUUCUCAUUAUAUACUUUUAACCUUCUGAAGUUUCAUUUGUAGUCUUUAGAUGUUAAAUGAAUUUCUAGGUAAUUCCUGGGAAAGAAGGAUGCUGAACCACUUGUGGGCUGGUAAAAACCCUGUCUAUUAGUCUUAAAGCAGAGUGCUCACUUUCUCUUUCCAACAGCUUCCAGUAAGUGGGCCCACGUCACACACUGGCCCCAGUGAUCGUAGUGUUGUAGGAAGCGCUGCCAUAUUUGAUUGAAUUUAGCCAUUCUGGAAUGACGUGUUCAUGAAGUCGGCUCUUGCAUUACCGUGGCCUUUAUUAUUGCUAAUGCAUUCUGACAUUACAGGUGUAGCCUUGGCUCUCCCAGAAAGGGCAAGGCUGCUCUUACCAAACGAAAGAGCAGAAUUUAUGAAACUGUUACACAGUGAGGCCAGUGUUCACCUUUAGUUACUAAGCAGAGUAAGGGAAAUAAAUGCUUUUAUAGAAAAGAUAGCCAGUGACAGCAGUCUAUCCUGAUUCCUCACCCAGCACUGUUUCAAAAAGUGGAUCAAUUAAUAUUGUUGCCAGACAGAGAACGAGGACCAAUGGUUAGGAGGUUCAGGAAAGUAGAUUUCAACUCAGUUUAAAGAGGCACUCCUGAAAAUGAGCUGACAGUCUCUUAAGGGAGUAGUUUCCCUGCUCAUUAUGAGCAUUCAAGAGGAGGCUUCCUGAUCAUUUGUCAGGGUUGUUGGAGAGGGGAGUCCCUAGGUCAUGGGUGGGACCAGAUGGCUCAAGAUCUCUUUUGGCUUGUUUCCUCAUCUUAGAUUGCUACAGCACAAACAGCAUCUUUCCUGCUUCUAUUUUGACUUUACAAGUGGCUGGUGUACCGUGAGGACCUGUGAAUGCUCAGUAGCUAUUCAUUAUUUAAUCUCUGGCUUCCUGCUUCUUAAUCUAACAUGAAUCAAAGCUGUUCUUGUUCAAUUCAGGAAAACCACCAUCUCUGGCACCUCCUAGAAUGAGGCAUUCUGGAUAGUUACGUUUUCUGGAUGGUCAUCAGGAGCCAUUUGAAAGCAGAACAAACAAAACACUUUAAAACUUUUGGCUGGGAAUUAUGUAAAAUGGAUUACAUACUUUCUUGCUUUAUUAAGCUGAAUAUCUGGAAUAUAAUUUAAUCGUGAUGACUCAGUAUUGUCAUUUUAGAUGAACGUGUUUAUAUGGUGUUAUAAGCAUAGCUGUGUUUUCAAAACCUGUUGAAAUAUAGAUGUGUUGUAUAUUUGCCCCUACUUGAAAUGACUCCACCGAUUCUAAAUGACCCCAGACUAAUAAGCUUUUUGAAUUUUUUUGUUUGCUUUUCAUGGAUGUUUCUCUCUUGGCAUUUGCUGUUGGGCUUUUUUUUGCUGUCACAUCUUUGUUUGGUGUUUCUGUACUAGCUGGCUCCUUCCUCUCUGUUCUUAUUUGCAGCUUUUAUCUUCUAUGAUUUGGAUACCAGAUAACUAAGCUUGUAUAUAAAAUAAAUAGUAAGUAGCGUGAGUAAAGCUUCGCAGCGUAUAAAAUAUAUGGAAUUUGUAAUAUCUUUUUUGGCUGCCCUGAUUUCUUCUGCUAUUCCCUGUCUCCUCCUUCUCUGUUGGUUUUCUCCUUUUUUUGAAUUGGGUGUCAGCUUGGAGAGAUGAAAUCUGGAAAGACUGGGUCUUGUCCUUGACCUAAGCCCAUAUCUCUGGCCCAGGUAUCAGCGACUGCCUCAUGGAAUCAACUUAGAAAUUAUAAAAUGGCACAGGUAGGGGGUCCUGAAGGUCAUCUGUUUAACCCCUUAUUUUAUAGCAGUGAAGGAAUCUGAGGCACUGAGUGGGGACAUAAGAGGCCAGGUUCAUGACAGUAUUUGUGUAAGGUAAAAAAAAAAAAAAAUCUUGUAGGAAAAUUCUCUGCUGGCUUAUCAGCAAGUUCAGAAUUAAAGUACAUAAACCAAAAAAAGGCUUCUGUUUGUGGCAGCGUUUGGCUGUGUUUGCACUCAAGACUAUUAUCGAUAUUCUAGGAGAAGCUUUAAUCCUUUCAUUCAAACUUACAAGAAAUGCUGUUUCCUUUUAGUUAAAAAAAAAAAAAAAAAAAAAAUCCAAGAGAGCAUUUGAUUUGAGGAACCAAAAGUCUAGAAAAUGUAUCCGGGAGUCCUCGUCAAUUUGGGGCAUAAUGAAAUAUAAAAAAUACUCAAUAAAAGCUCCUUUAUUACUUUAACUGUUUAAAUGUGGAGUUUUUAGCCAUCAGGUUAAUGUUUUGGUAUCAUUUUUUUAUUUGAUUGUGAGCACUUUUCCAGGUAGCUCUGCCACUCGAGCGCUAAUCAGAUUCCCACAGAUAAAUGGUGCUAGCUGCAGCCUGACAUCACUGCGUUUUUGCUUCAACAUUAUUUUAUUUUAUUUGGUUUUCCUGUAAAAGUUAAUAACUCCAUGUCCAUGUGUUUAAACAGGCAAGAAGAGAGAGAGAGAAAGGACAGUGAGCAGAAAAGGAUGAGGGAUGUUUCAGGAAGCUUGUGCAAAAUUGAGGAAAUUUAGGGAUUUUUGUAAUUUCCAGACAGAGCUGGGAAGAAUUUGAAAGGAGUUACCAUUGAUUUAAAGGAGGAAGAUGCUCAAUAAACUGAUUUGCUUAAUGAUUGCCACGGCAGUGAAGUUUCUACAGAAUUCCCGGGUCCGCCAGAGCCCACUUGCAACCAGGAGAGCAUUCCUAAAGAAGAAAGGGCUGACAGAUGAAGAGAUUGAUAUGGCCUUCCAGCAGUCGGGCACUGCUGCCGAUGAGCCUUCGUCCUUGGGCCCAGCCACACAGGUGGUUCCUGUCCAGCCCCCUCACCUCAUAUCUCAGCCAUACAGUCCCGCAGGCUCCCGAUGGCGAGAUUACGGCGCCCUGGCCAUCAUCAUGGCAGGCAUUGCAUUUGGCUUUCACCAGCUCUACAAGAAAUACCUGCUCCCCCUCAUCCUGGGCGGCCGAGAGGACAGAAAGCAGCUGGAGAGGAUGGAGGCCGGUCUCUCUGAGCUGAGUGGCAGCGUGGCCCAGACAGUGACUCAGUUACAGACGACCCUCGCCUCCGUCCAGGAGCUGCUGAUUCAGCAGCAGCAGAAGAUCCAGGAGCUUGCCCACGAGCUGGCCGCUGCCAAGGCCACCACAUCCACCAACUGGAUCCUGGAGUCCCAGAAUAUCAACGAACUCAAGUCCGAAAUUAACUCCUUGAAAGGGCUUCUUUUAAAUCGGAGGCAGUUCCCUCCAUCCCCAUCAGCCCCGAAGAUCCCCUCCUGGCAGAUCCCAGUCAAGUCACCGUCACCCUCCAGCCCUGCGGCCGUGAACCACCACAGCAGCAGCGACAUCUCACCUGUCAGCAACGAGUCCACGUCGUCCUCGCCUGGGAAGGAGGGCCACAGCCCCGAGGGCUCCACGGUCACCUACCACUUGCUGGGCCCCCAGGAGGAAGGCGAGGGGGUGGUGGACGUCAAGGGCCAGGUGCGGAUGGAGGUGCAAGGCGAGGAGGAGAAGAGGGAGGACAAGGAGGACGAGGAGGAUGAGGAGGAUGAUGAUGUGAGCCAUGUGGACGAGGAGGACUGCCUGGGGGUGCAGAGGGAGGACCGCCGGGGCGGGGAUGGGCAGAUCAACGAGCAGGUGGAGAAGCUGCGGCGGCCCGAGGGCGCCAGCAACGAGAGUGAGCGGGACUAGGGCUGCGCCUGCUGCCUCCAGCCCUGAGGAUGGCAUCUAGUGUGCCCGUGCGUGGCCAUACCCUGCCUCCCUCUCUGGCCCUGGGAGGGCAGCUUGGAGCCCAGGUAGGGGGCAGAGCUGUCCUCAGCUGCACUGCGGCCUGGUGGCAGUGUGGGGAGUCACACUUCUGUCCACCUGGCCUCCUCUCGCCUGGCCGCCAGCCCCAGCCCCAGCCCCAGCCCCAGGCCCAGCUGCCUUUGGCUUUGAUCUCAAGUCAGGCUGAAGGCAGCGAAGCCUCGGGGCCCAAGCCCCUCCCCAGCCCCCUCUCCCGGACAGACGCCUUGCCCAGGGUGUGUUUGCUGAGUGUCUUGACUACCGUGACACCACGCAUGGCCAGAGCUAGCGUCCCUACUGCCUCCCGACUCCUCAGUGGAGGAGGAGCUGCGGUCCCUCUGGUGUCUGCCAUCCCCCUCCCUCCCUGGGCCCGGCCCUGGACCCGUCAGGUGCCUGUCCCCAGCCCCAACCCCACUCAUGCCCCGUCGUCCUCCCAGACAAAUGAAACCACGCUGCGCUUCCGAUGCCCCCGCUUGCCGUGUAAUGGUUCAGCUAAUCCCAUGGCGAGAUGGGGGCUCACUCCGGAGGAGGAGCCAGGCAGCAGGGCCUUCCUGACCAACAGCCAGCUCUGUCCUUCCCCCCAGGAAACACAUGUUCAUUUGUGUGAUCAUGUAUAGACCUCAGAACGGAAGAUAGGACUGUAUAUAAUUGUAAUAAAUACCAGUUGCCACUAUUUAA